GUACCUGGUUUUUGUUGUCAGCUGGUUAGACAUGUCUGGUCGCGGCAAAGGCGGUAAAGGUUUGGGUAAGGGAGGUGCCAAGCGUCACCGAAAAGUGCUGCGGGAUAACAUCCAAGGCAUCACCAAACCGGCCAUUCGGCGCCUUGCUAGGCGUGGUGGGGUUAAGCGAAUUUCCGGUUUGAUUUAUGAGGAGACUCGUGGCGUUCUCAAGGUGUUUCUGGAGAACGUGAUCCGGGACGCCGUGACCUACACGGAGCACGCCAAGCGCAAGACUGUCACUGCCAUGGAUGUGGUUUACGCGCUCAAGCGUCAAGGACGCACUCUGUACGGCUUCGGCGGUUAAUCUUUUCGUCAGUUUUCUUCCAAUGGCCCUUUUCAGGGCCGCCCA